GCUCUUCUUCCUUCCUUCUCCAGUCCCUUCCACUGUGCGUCUUCUGUCCCCCGUUCUUCCCCAGCGGACCCCUCUUUCGAGACUCCCUAGUGGGGUCCCCAGCUCCCGGGCGAUCCUGCCCUUGCCGAGCGCGUUUUCUGGAGUCACCUGGGGGAGGGGAGUCCUGGGCAGGGCCGGGCUGGGGAAGACGCCUGGGGCACUGCCCGGCGUUAACAAAGGGAGCCGAUACCGACCGGCGUGGGCGCGGAGCGGGCGGCCGCCACCGAGCGUGCUGAGCAACCGCAGCCUCCGCGGCCGAGAGUGCAGCGAGCAAGGGGAGAGCCAGUUGCGCAGAGCCCUGCAACCAGCAGUCCAGGGAGAAGUGGUGAAUGUCAUGGAGCCCAGCUGAAAUGGACUGGCCCCCUUGAGCCUGUCCCAAGCCCUGGUGCCAGGUGUCCAUCCCCGUGCUGAGAUGAGUUUUGAUCAUCCUGAGAAAAAUGGGCCUUGGCCUGCAGACCCAAUAAACCUUCCCUCCCAUGGAUAAUAGUGCUAAUUCCUGAGGACCUGAAGGGCCUGCCGCCCCUGGGGGAUUAGCCAGAAGCAGGCUUGUUUUCCUGCUCAGAACAAAGUGACUUCCCUGAACACAUCUUCAUUAUGAUUCACACCAACCUGAAGAAAAAGUUCAGCUGCUGCGUCCUGGUCUUUCUUCUGUUUGCAGUCAUCUGUGUGUGGAAGGAAAAGAAGAAAGGGAGUUACUAUGAUUCCUUUAAAUUGCAAACCAAGGAAUUCCAGGUGUUAAAGAGUCUGGGGAAAUUGGCCAUGGGGUCUGAUUCCCAGUCUGUAUCCUCAAGCAGCACCCAGGACCCCCACAGGGGCCGCCAGACCCUCGGCAGUCUCAGAGGCCUAGCCAAGGCCAAACCAGAGGCCUCCUUCCAGGUGUGGAACAAGGACAGCUCUUCCAAAAACCUUAUCCCUAGGCUGCAAAAGAUCUGGAAGAAUUACCUAAGCAUGAACAAGUACAAAGUGUCCUACAAGGGGCCAGGACCAGGCAUCAAGUUCAGUGCAGAGGCCCUGCGCUGCCACCUCCGGGACCAUGUGAAUGUAUCCAUGGUAGAGGUCACAGAUUUUCCCUUCAAUACCUCUGAAUGGGAGGGUUAUCUGCCCAAGGAGAGCAUUAGGACCAAGGCUGGGCCUUGGGGCAGGUGUGCUGUUGUGUCGUCAGCGGGAUCUCUGAAGUCCUCCCAACUAGGCAGAGAAAUCGAUGAUCAUGACGCAGUCCUGAGGUUUAAUGGGGCACCCACAGCCAACUUCCAACAAGAUGUGGGCACAAAAACUACCAUUCGCCUGAUGAACUCUCAGUUGGUUACCACAGAGAAGCGCUUCCUCAAAGACAGUUUGUACAAUGAAGGAAUCCUAAUUGUAUGGGACCCAUCUGUAUACCACUCAGAUAUCCCAAAGUGGUACCAGAAUCCGGAUUAUAAUUUCUUUAACAACUACAAGACUUAUCGUAAGCUGCACCCCAAUCAGCCCUUUUACAUCCUCAAGCCCCAGAUGCCUUGGGAGCUAUGGGACAUUCUUCAAGAAAUCUCCCCAGAAGAGAUUCAGCCAAACCCCCCAUCCUCUGGGAUGCUUGGUAUCAUCAUCAUGAUGACGCUGUGUGACCAGGUGGAUAUUUAUGAGUUCCUCCCAUCCAAGCGCAAGACUGACGUGUGCUACUACUACCAGAAGUUCUUCGAUAGUGCCUGCACGAUGGGUGCCUACCACCCGCUGCUCUAUGAGAAGAAUUUGGUGAAGCAUCUCAACCAGGGCACAGAUGAGGACAUCUACCUGCUUGGAAAAGCCACACUGCCUGGCUUCCGGACCAUUCACUGCUAAGCACAGGCUCCUCACUCUUCUCCAUCAGGCAUUAAAUGAAUGGUCUCUUGGCCACCCCAGCCUGGGAAGAACAUUUUCCUGAACAAUUCCAGCCUGCUCCUUUUACUCUAGGGGCCUCUGUCAGCAAGACCAUGGGGACUUCAAGAGCCUGUGGUCAGGAAAUCAGGUCCAGCCUUCCCUGUAGCCAGACAGUUUAUGAGCCCAGAGCCUCCUGCCACACACAUGCACACAUAUCUAGCAUUCUUUCCAGACAGCAUCCUCCCCGCCUUCCACCUUGGUAGAUGCAAGGUCUAUCUCUCCCAUCAGGGCUGCCAAAGCUGGGCUUUGUUUUUCCCAGCAGAAUGAUGCCAUUCUCACAAACCAAUGCUCUAUAUUGCUUGAAGUCUGCAUCUAAAUAUUGAUUUCACGUUUUAAAGAAAUUCUCUUAAAUUACAAUUGUGCCCAAUGCAGGGUGGCUCUGGGGGGCAAGUAGGUGGUACAGGGGAUUGGAAACAUGCUCCGCGCCUCCAGAGAAAAGUUGCUCCCGAGGUCCAUGCCCCUGGAACGUGUUCCUAUCACUCUGGCUGGUUGGGCUGGUCCUUAGACUGGGUGCUUAUGAUUAAAGGGUCUUGGUUAGCCCACUUUCCCUCUCCAUGUGGAGAUGGAAGGUAGAGAAGGAUACAGUGUCUAUCCUCAAGUUGCUACGGUUCAGUGAGAGAGGCAGACAUCUGAACAGGCAGGUAGGAUUCAGUGUGCUCAGUGCACUGGGGAUUUGGAGAGAGAUGGGCUUGCUCUCUCUGUGCACCCAGGAGGGCCACGCACUUAAAACUGUGUUUGUGGAUCAGAGAAGGCUUUAUAGCACAGGGGGCAUUCAGAUGAGUCUUAGAGGAAGAGAAGAAACAUGGCAAGCAGAUUACAUCUGAGCCGUUUGAAUUGUGUUUUUCUUUCUUCCCAUGUUUAUUUUCUAAGAUCUACCUGAACUUAGAGACUCAAGAUAUUUUUUUAGGAAACCUCCUACCCAUGUCUGAGGUAGCAAGUGCAGCCUCACGACAGAUACCAGGCAAUCCAGAGCCACAAAACGUGAUUCCUCCAGGCUCUGCCUGGCCUGACCCUGUCCUGUCAGCUGGGUUUACAUACCAGUCCCAUUCUUCCUUUUCAAUACCUACCCCCAAAUCUUCUCCUAACCACCAUCUGUUUUUUUUUUUUAAAGCAUUUUUUGCUUUAAAAGCAUCCUGACCCCAAUUUCUUUGAGCUCACGGGCCUUUUGCUGAAGGUCUCUCAGGGUGUAGUGGUGUGGCUCUCUGGACUUAACGUCACUCUCAGAGGUCAGAACCUUGGAGAUCAGAACUGAUUCUCACCAGGUGUGAGAGGUGUGGUAGCAGAUUGCAAUGCUCUGCACCUCUUCCUUGCAAGUGAGCAACUUCAGGCUCUCUGGGCAGAGGCUGGCCCACUGUAGUUUGCAGACAUGCUCUCCAGAUGGUUUUACUAAGUCCCCUCUCCCUGAUAGGGAAUCCUGCUGGACCAGCGCAGCCCUGGUGUGGAGAGGUUAAAAGACUUGCACAGGAUCACCAAGUCAUGCUGUAGAGCCAGGAUUCCUAGACCCAGGGCUCUGCACUCUCAAGGCUGGCCCCAUGUGCUCAAGGGGAUCUAAUGUUUGGGCUCCAAACUAACCAUCUCGGAGCUGGGCUCCUCAUUUACUGCCAAACCCUCAGCUUAUGUAGCUAGAAAGGGCCCUGGAGUGAGAAAGCCUGGAUUUUCAAAUUGAUGCUCCCCUACUGACUAGCUGUGCCACUCUGGGCAAAUGCUCUUCCUUGAGCCUGUUUCCACACCUGUAAAGUGGGGAUGAUGAUCCUAUCUCACUGCUUUUGUGAGGAUUACAGGAAAGCACCUGUCCUGGCUCUGUACCUGGCACGUAGUAGGUGCUCAGUUCAUGCUGGUUUCCUUCCUGCCUUUAGUAGGGACCUGCUCUGUGCUCACACCUCGGCUGCAUGCACCCUGCUGUGACGGAGGCUAGUGUGGAAGAGGUCCUGUCCUCAGGGAAUUAACUGUCUUAUUGGGAGACAACAACUGUCCUCCUUGGAACACCCAAGAAACCAUGCAAAGCAGUGGACAACACAGAACACGCCCUCCUCCUCGCUGCCUGCAGCUCCAAUCUGAUUCUGCUUGGGAAUGGGCGGAGCACGUGGGCUGCUUAACUGCUGUAUAGGACAAGCCCCUUACCCCUCUCUGGGCCCAUGAAUUCCUGGCUUGGUUUAUGUUCUGAUUUGACACACUGAUUUUAAUCUUCGAAUCAUGACACUGAGUGCAGAGGAGGUGGCAUUCCGACAGCAGGACAUACAUGUUGGUGUGAAGACUGGGACGACACUGGGUAGAAUCUAGUUUUUAAUUAUUAUUAAUAUAAAGGAUCAAAUUAAUUUAAAUAUGAUUCUGAAGUCUACAGAACUUUUAGUUCUGUGCUGUCUAUGUGGACACUUUGGUAAAAUGCAAAUUAUGAUAUGGACGUUAUCAUUGGUCUGGUGAGAUGUUUCAUAUUUGUGACAGUUAAUUUAAAAAUUAUGAGUUAAUGCUGCCUGUGUCUAUGGGGUUCUGUCUUCUUUGAUAGCCAUCUAUUCAUCUGGAUCAUGGGACCCUCUCUAAUCCUUCCACCAAUCAAAUAAGCUAUUGCUAUUGGUUUGGAGUUGAGAUAUCAGUCUCGGAAACUUCUGAAAAAUGCUAAUAAUUACCCAAGGAUUAUGUCAAAUUUUAAAAUAAAUGUGUGUGUGUUUCUUUAA